GAGGCGGCUGGGGACCGCGGGGCGGACGGGAGCGAGUAUGUCCGCUCUGACUCGGCUGGCGUCUUUCGCUCGCGUUGGAGGCCGCCUUUUCAGAAGCGGCUGCGCACGGACUGCUGGAGAUGGUGGAGUCCGUCAUGCCGGUGGUGGUGUGCACAUUGAGCCCCGGUAUAGACAGUUCCCCCAGCUGACCAGAUCCCAGGUGUUCCAGAGCGAGUUCUUCAGCGGACUCAUGUGGUUCUGGAUUCUCUGGCGCUUUUGGCAUGACUCAGAAGAGGUGCUGGGUCACUUUCCGUAUCCUGAUCCUUCCCAGUGGACAGAUGAAGAAUUAGGUAUCCCUCCUGAUGAUGAAGACUGAAGGUGUAGACUCAGCCUCACUCUGUACAAGAGCCAGGUGAGAAUUUCAAGGAUUAUCGACUUCAUAUUGCACAUUAAAGUUACAAAUUAAAGUGGCUUGGUCAAGAAUGA